AUUGUGUGCGGGGCUCCUCCGCACGGCGAGGCGCGGGCGCUGCUCUCCGCUCCGCCAGGCCGCCGCCAGACUCUGGCCACGGCCCGCGCGCUCCUCGCCUCUCGCUUCCGCACCGCCCCACAGCCCCGCCGCCGCCGUGCCGCCGCCGCCGCCGCCGCCUCCUCGGACGCUAAGCUCAGCCAGCCGGCUCUCGCCGCACUCCCGCCCGGCCCGCACUCUGCGCCGCAGGAAGGGGAGGGCCGGGGGGAGGUGGCCGCGGCGCGGAUGACGGAGCCAGGCGGGCCUCUUAAAGGGGCCGCGCCGUGGGCACAGGGCGGGGGGGCCCCCUGGAGGCGGCUCCCCCAUCGAGCCGCCACCCUCCCCCCGUCCCUGUGCCUUUUGGGAAACUGAGGCCCUAACAACAGCGAAUUGGACUGUGCAACUCGCAGCCCAGGGGUCCCCCGUAAAAAAGACACCGGACUCCCUGGUCCAUAAAGACCUUUCCAAUACAGAGGUCUGGGCCAGUUCUGCAGUCCUGGAACAGGAACACUUGGCUCCCCUCCGGCCAGGAGGACUUCUCCGGCCAGUCCAGCCGCGUGUCCCCAAGCCCCACCACCUACCUCAUGUUCCGGGACAAGAGCUGCUCUCUCUGGCAGAACUCGCAGCAGUCCUCCGACAGAAGCAACCUCCCCCCUCUGCCCCUACCACGCCGCAGUGCCAUAAGCGUCACCGGCACUGCCCAGUCGUCGUGUCAGAGGCCACCAUCGUGGGCAUCUGCAAGACCAGGCAGAUCUGGCCCAACGAUGCGGAGGGCACCUUCCAUGGAGACGCAGUGAGUGGUUUCUGCAGAGCUUCAUUUGGAAAGGCCUCUGUAGUUGGGGAAAGAUGGCCCAUUCCCAGAACUCCUUGGAGCUUCCCAUUAACAUCAAUGCCACCCAGAUUACCACUGCCUAUGGCCAUCGGGCCCUGCCCAAGCUGAAGGAGGAGCUGCAGUCAGAGGACCUCCAGACGAGGCAGAAAGCCCUCAUGGCCUUGUGUGACCUCAUGCAUGACCCCGAGUGUAUCUACAAGGCCAUGAACAUAGGCUGUAUGGAGAACCUGAAAGCUUUGCUGAAGGAUAGCAACAGUAUGGUGCGCAUAAAGACCACCGAGGUGCUCCACAUCACGGCAAGCCAUAGCGUGGGCAGAUACGCCUUUCUAGAGCACGACAUCGUCCUUGCCCUGUCCUUCCUGCUGAAUGACCCCAGCCCAGUCUGCCGGGGGAACCUGUACAAGGCAUACAUGCAGCUGGUCCAGGUGCCUAGAGGGGCCCAAGAGAUCAUCAGCAAAGGUCUGAUUUCCUCACUGGUAUGGAAGCUGCAGGUGGAGGUGGAGGAGGAGGAGUUCCAGGAGUUCAUCCUGGACACACUGGUCCUCUGCCUGCAGGAGGAUGCCACCGAGGCCCUGGGCAGCAAUGUGGUGCUUGUCCUGAAGCAGAAGCUCCUCAGCGCCAACCAGAACAUCCGCAGCAAGGCCGCCCGUGCGCUCCUUAAUGUCAGCAUAUCUCGAGAGGGCAAGAAACAGGUGUGUCAUUUUGACGUCAUCCCCAUCCUGGUCCAUCUGCUGAAAGACCCAGUGGAGCAUGUGAAGUCUAACGCUGCCGGUGCCCUGAUGUUCGCCACAGUGAUCACUGAAGAGAUGGAAUCUCAUUAUGUUGCCCAGGCUGGUCUUGAACUCCUGGGCAGGAUACGAGGGUGGAUGGAGAGGAGCCAGUUGAGGCCGGAAAGGCAGGAGAUGAAGAGGCCAGGCCCAGGCCGGACUCAGCGAAGGGAAGUAUGCGGCCCUGGAGGCACAAGCCAUCGGCCUGCUCCUGGAGCUGCUGCACUCCCCCAUGACCAUAGCGCGCCUGAAUGCCACCAAGGCCCUUACCAUGCUGGCAGAGGCCCCCGAGGGCCGCAAGGCCCUGCAGACGCACGUGCCCACUUUCCGUGCCAUGGAGGUGGAGACUUACGAAAAGCCUCAAGUGGCCGAAGCCUUACAGCGGGCAGCCCGGAUCGCCAUCAGUGUCAUCGAGUUCAAACCCUGAGCCCUUCAUUCACCUCUGUGAGUGAAUAAAUGUGCUAAGUCUCUUUA